CACAGCAAGACUCUAUCUCCAAAAAAAAAAAAAAAAUCAGUGAUAGAACAAGAAGAAAUUUAAAUGCUGGGCUUUUCAUAUAAAUCCAGGGAAUUAUGGGACAGUUAGUACCCACCUCCCAGGGUGUUAUGAGGAUAAAUUCACAUUAUGUCAUCUUCCCAGCACAAUGCUCUAUAGUGUGCUUCUGAGCACACAGCGCAUGCUCCAUAAACAUCGCAUUAAUGCAUGUGCGCGUGUUGUUUUCCAAAUGCAGACUUACUCAGACAUGAGCUGCCUCUGGAAACUUUAAAGGACCAACAGAGAACGCCAUGUUUUAGAAUAGUGAUUGGUGGUUUUUAUUUUGGACCAAAAGCAUUUGUGUUCUAAGAAGAGUGUAGGUAUAAGGGACUGUGUGCUGUGGCGCUUUGUCUAGUUGAGUGCUGUUAUAAGUGAUCUAGGGCAAGCAGGGUCAGCAUUAGCUGUGAAUGAAGCCAAUCCGUGGACUCCUUUCAAGCCUGCAGAAUUGACUGGGCACGGUGACUCACACCUGUAAUCCCAGCACUUUGGGAGGCUGAGAAGGGCGGAUCACCUGAGGUCAGGAGUUCAAGACCAGCCUAGCCAAUAUCGUGAAAGGCCAUCUCUACUAAAAACACAAAAAUUAGCCACCCGGGCAUGGUGGCAUGUGACUGUAGUCUCAGCUACUUGGGAGGCUGAGGCAGGAGAAUCACUUGAGCCUGGGAGGCAAAGAUUGCAGUGAGCCGAGAUCACGCCAGUGCACUCCAGCCUGGGCGACAGAGUAAGACUCUGUCUCAAACAAACAAACCUGCAGAAUCAAAUUAGUCUGGGGCUUGAAAUACCAGAUGAUUUCUCCGAAUAUUAAAGUUUAAGAGGCAAUUCUUAGCUAAGUGAUUGUCAGCUCAUCACAUUCUAGUUAGGAUUAAAUGGCCAGUUUGAAGAAAUACCCUUACCUGUGUCCUCUCGACGGAUUAUGUUGGCCUGGGUGGAAGCAUCCAUAUUGUUUUAAUUAAGUGUCCCAUGUAAUUGUAAGAUAAAGCCAGAGGCAAUCAUGAGGGCUCCCAGACAUAAGUGAGAAUUGAGUUCAGCCUUUUUGUGUGUGUGAGACAGUCUCACUCCGUCACCCAGGCCCCAGGCUGGAGUGCAGUGGCGCGAUCUUGGCUCACUGCAACCUCUGUCUCCUGGGCUCAAGUGAUUCUCCUGACUCAGCCUCCCCAGGCUUUGUUUUUUUUUUUUGUUUUUGUUUUUCUUUUUUGUUUUUUUAGAUGGAGUUUCGCUCUUGUUGCCCAGGCUGGAGUGCAAUGGUGCGAUCUCGGCUCACCACAACCUCUGCCUCCUGGGUUCAAGUGAUUCUCCUGCCUCAGCCUCCCAAGUAGCUGGGAUUACAGGCAUGCGCCACCACACUCGGCUAAUUUUGUAUUUUUAGUAGAGACAAGGUUUCUCCAUGUUGGUCAGCCUGGUCACAAACUCCCGAUCUCAGAUGAUCUGCCUGCCUUGGCCUCCCAGAGUGUUGGGAUUACAGGCAUGAGCCAUAGCGCCUAGCCCCCAGGCUUUGUUUUAAAGAGAGGUCAUGGGGCCUGCUGUGCUUGGUUUUCAUGGGAGCAGGGGAGUGGGGCCCUAUGGGCCCUUUGCUGCAGCAGAAAUUGCUGCCAUCUCUGGCAUGGAAGGGCAUCUAAAGGCAGGAAACUGGAGACUCACAUUUUAGUCUUUAGGUAGAAGCUCACUGUUCCUGAAAUUCUCCUGUGACAAUGACAAAGGACAAGCAAGUGUGGCCUUUUCUGUGCCUUUAAGAUAAUAUCACCUGAGAAGGAAUCCCAAAGGGAAGAGCAAGAGGAAGAAAUGGCUGGUUCUCAGGAACUGUUGACAUUCAGGGAUGUGACCAUAGAAUUCUCUCUGGAGGAGUGGGAGUUUCUGAACCCUGCUCAGCAGAGUUUGUAUAGGAAAGUGAUGCUAGAGAACUACAGAAACCUGGUCUCUCUGGGUCUUACUGUUUCUAAGCCAGAACUGAUUAGCCGUCUGGAGCAAAGACAGGAGCCCUGGAAUGUGAAGAGACAUGAGACCAUAGCCAAACCCCCAGCUAUGUCUUCUCAUUACACUGAAGACCUUUUGCCAGAACAGUGCAUGCAAGAUUCAUUCCAAAAAGUGAUACUGAGAAGAUAUGGAAGCUGUGGACUUGAGGAUUUACACUUAAGGAAGGAUGGGGAAAAUGUGGGUGAGUGUAAGGAUCAAAAAGAAAUUUAUAAUGGACUUAACCAAUGUUUGUCAACUCUACCUAGCAAAAUUUUCCCAUAUAAUAAAUGUGUGAAAGUCUUUAGUAAAUCAUCAAAUCUAAAUAGAGAAAACAUAAGACAUACUACAGAGAAACUUUUCAAAUGUAUGCAAUGUGGCAAAGUCUUUAAAUCUCACUCAGGCCUUUCUUAUCAUAAGAUAAUUCACACUGAAGAGAAACUCUGCAUAUGUGAGGAAUGUGGCAAAACCUUUAAGUGGUUCUCAUACCUUACUAAACAUAAGAGAAUUCACACUGGAGAGAAACCAUACAAAUGUGAAGAAUGUGGCAAAGCUUUUAACUGGUGCUCGAGUCUUACUAAACAUAAGAGAAUCCAUACUGGUGAGAAACCCUACAAAUGUGAAGAAUGUGGAAAAGCCUUUCACUGGUGUUCACCCUUUGUUAGACAUAAGAAAAUUCAUACAGGAGAAAAACCCUAUACAUGUGAAGACUGUGGCAGAGCGUUUAACCGGCACUCACAUCUCACCAAACAUAAGACAAUUCACACUGGAAAGAAACCCUACAAAUGUAAAGAAUGUGGGAAAGCCUUUAACCACUGCUCACUACUUACUAUACAUGAGAGAACCCAUACGGGAGAGAAACCCUAUAAAUGUGAAGAAUGUGGCAAAGCUUUUAACUCAUCAUCAAUUCUUACUGAACAUAAGGUAAUUCAUAGCGGAGAGAAACCCUACAAAUGUGAAAAAUGUGACAAAGUCUUUAAGAGGUUCUCAUACCUUACUAAACACAAGAGAAUUCACACUGGAGAGAAACCCUACAAAUGUGAAGAAUGUGGCAAAGCUUUUAACUGGUCCUCAAUCCUUACUGAACAUAAGAGAAUUCAUACUGGAGAGAAACCCUACAACUGUGAAGAAUGUGGAAAAGCCUUUAAUCGGUGCUCACACCUUACUAGACAUAAGAAAAUUCAUACUGCCGUCAAACGCUAUAAAUGUGAAGAAUGUGGCAAAGCUUUUAAACGGUGCUCACAUCUUAAUGAACAUAAGAGAGUUCAAAGAGGAGAGAAAUCCUGCAAGUAUAAAAAAUGUGGGGAAGCUUUUAAUCACUGCUCAAACCUUACUACGUAAGAAUUUUUACUAAAGAGAAAUCCUACAAAUGUAAAGAAUGUGGCAAAUUCCAUAAAUCUUGCUCAAGGCAUUGAAAUCACAAGAUAAUUCAUACUGGAGAGAAACACUACAAAUGUGAAGAAUGUGGGGAAAGUCUUCAACCAUUGCUGACAGCUUAUUGCACAGAAGAAAAUUCAUGCUGAGAAAAAUUCUGAUUUUAAAGAAUGUGGCAAAGCAUUUAAUAACUACUAUGAACUUACUCAUCAGAGGUUUUGUGCUAGAUAAAAGCAAUGUAAGUGUAAUGAUACACAUUACAUUUAUCUGUGGAAAGAUGUCACCAAAUAAAAGCCUUAGAGUACACAAGGUGUAAUGAUAGUGAUACAUUACAUUUGUACAUGGAAAGACUUCAAAAAUAUAAGCCUUAGAGUACACAAGAGUUUUUAUACUGAAGAAAAACAUUACAAAUAUAAAGAUUGUUGCAAUACUUUUACUUAUGUUACAGAUUUUGUUGUACAUAGGAGAAUUUAUACUGAAAGGUAACCCUCUAACAGUUGCUCAAAUUUUAUUCCAUUUUAGAUAAUUUACAUUGGAAAGAAACCCUACAACUGUAAUGAAUAUGAAAAAAAUUGUUUAAAAAGUACACCUUAGAAAACACUAGUUUAAGGCCGGGCGCGGUGGCUCACACUUAUAAUCCCAGCACUUUGGGAGGCCGAGGCAGGCGGAUCACGAGGUCAGGAGAUCGAGACCACGAUGAAACCCUGUCUCUACUAAAAAUACAAAAAAUUAGCUGGGCAUGUUGUCGGGUGCCUGUAGUCCCAGCUACUGGGAGAGGCUGAGGCAGGAGAAUGGCGUGAACCCGAGAGGCGGAGCUUGCAGUGAGCCGAGAUCGCGCCACUGAACUCCAACCUGGGCGACAGAGACUCUGUCUCAAAAAAAAAGAAAGAACGCUAGUUUAUAUGAAAGCAUUUAACAGAUGCAGUAAAUAUAAAAAAUUAAUAAAAAAUUAAGUCUAAAUGAACAUCAGAAGAUUCACAGUAGAAACCACUAAGACGCUAACACUUUCAAUGUUAUUCUAAAUCAGGGCAUUGAUUAUAAAGAGUAAUUCAAGGUUAACAUAAUUUAGUUAGCCUAAACAGAAAUAGGAGAUUAAUAUUUUGAGACUUAAACAAUUAUAUUCAAAGUACACUUUUUGCAUUGAAAGAAUUUUAGAUUUUUACAAAGGCAAAUUUUGAUGUAAUUGAACUCUCAAAUUACUUGAUGCUGUGUCUUUAUUCCUAGUGUCUGUAUGAAAGCAUGUGGUCAAUUUCUGCUGCUCGGGGUUUGAGAAGUUCUAUAUUAGGAUGUCAUUUACAUACUUUUCAACAGAAGAUUGAGGACACUGAAAUAUGAGGUGUGUGAAGAAAGUACACAGAGAAACUUUUGUGGUUGACUUAUAAAACUUGUAAGUGCUGCAUGAGAUAGAUGUUCAGAGUAAUAGUCUUGUGCAUUAUUCAAAUUUUAGUAAAUUGUUUUACCAAUUGCACAUUAGAUAGUAUAGUGGAUUUUGUAAUGCUUUUCUUAGACUGUGUGAACUUAGUUUCAAUAAAACAAUUAUUUUUAAUGUGUUAA